GCAGUGGCUGGAGCCCUGGGCGCUGCAAAGCGUGUCCCGCCGGGUCCCCGAGCGUCCCGCGCCCUCGCCCCGCCAUGCUCCUGCUGCUGGGGCUGUGCCUGGGGCUGUCCCUGUGUGUGGGGUCGCAGGAAGAGGCGCAGAGCUGGGGCCACUCUUCGGAGCAGGAUGGACUCAGGGUCCCGAGGCAAGUCAGACUGUUGCAGAGGCUGAAAACCAAACCUUUGAUGACAGAAUUCUCAGUGAAGUCUACCAUCAUUUCCCGUUAUGCCUUCACUACGGUUUCCUGCAGAAUGCUGAACAGAGCUUCUGAAGACCAGGACAUUGAGUUCCAGAUGCAGAUUCCAGCUGCAGCUUUCAUCACCAACUUCACUAUGCUUAUUGGAGACAAGGUGUAUCAGGGCGAAAUUACAGAGAGAGAAAAGAAGAGUGGUGAUAGGGUAAAAGAGAAAAGGAAUAAAACCACAGAAGAAAAUGGAGAGAAGGGGACUGAAAUAUUCAGAGCUUCUGCAGUGAUUCCCAGCAAGGACAAAGCCGCCUUUUUCCUGAGUUAUGAGGAGCUUCUGCAGAGGCGCCUGGGCAAGUACGAGCACAGCAUCAGCGUGCGGCCCCAGCAGCUGUCCGGGAGGCUGAGCGUGGACGUGAAUAUCCUGGAGAGCGCGGGCAUCGCAUCCCUGGAGGUGCUGCCGCUUCACAACAGCAGGCAGAGGGGCAGUGGGCGCGGGGAAGAUGAUUCUGGGCCUCCCCCAUCUACUGUCAUUAACCAAAAUGAAACAUUUGCCAACAUAAUUUUUAAACCUACUGUAGUACAACAAGCCAGGAUUGCCCAGAAUGGAAUUUUGGGAGACUUUAUCAUUAGAUAUGACGUCAAUAGAGAACAGAGCAUUGGGGACAUCCAGGUUCUAAAUGGCUAUUUUGUGCACUACUUUGCUCCUAAAGACCUUCCUCCUUUACCCAAGAAUGUGGUAUUCGUGCUUGACAGCAGUGCUUCUAUGGUGGGAACCAAACUCCGGCAGGACAUUGGUUUCUCCCUCGCUGUCCAAAAUUGGGUUCCCAAGGGCUAUUUGGAUAUUUCAUGUGUAACCUUACAGACCAAGGAUGCCCUCUUCACAAUUCUCCAUGACCUCCGACCCCAGGACCGUUUCAGUAUCAUUGGAUUUUCCAACCGGAUCAAAGUAUGGAAGGACCACUUGAUAUCAGUCACUCCAGACAGCAUCAGGGAUGGGAAAGUGUACAUUCACCAUAUGUCACCCACUGGAGGCACAGACAUCAACGGGGCCCUGCAGAGGGCCAUCAGGCUCCUCAACAAGUACGUGGCCCACAGUGGCAUUGGAGACCGGAGCGUGUCCCUCAUCGUCUUCCUGACGGAUGGGAAGCCCACGGUCGGGGAGACGCACACCCUCAAGAUCCUCAACAACACCCGAGAGGCCGCCCGAGGCCAAGUCUGCAUCUUCACCAUUGGCAUCGGCAACGACGUGGACUUCAGGCUGCUGGAGAAACUGUCGCUGGAGAACUGUGGCCUCACACGGCGCGUGCACGAGGAGGAGGACGCAGGCUCGCAGCUCAUCGGGUUCUACGAUGAAAUCAGGACCCCGCUCCUCUCUGACAUCCGCAUCGAUUAUCCCCCCAGCUCAGUGGUGCAGGCCACCAAGACCCUGUUCCCCAACUACUUCAACGGCUCGGAGAUCAUCAUUGCGGGGAAGCUGGUGGACAGGAAGCUGGAUCACCUGCACGUGGAGGUCACCGCCAGCAACAGUAAGAAAUUCAUCAUCCUGAAGACAGAUGUGCCUGUGCGGCCUCAGAAGGCAGGGAAAGAUGUCACAGGAAGCCCCAGGCCUGGAGGCGAUGGAGAGGGGGACACCAACCACAUCGAGCGUCUCUGGAGCUACCUCACCACAAAGGAGCUGCUGAGCUCCUGGCUGCAAAGUGACGAUGAACCGGAGAAGGAGCGGCUGCGGCAGCGGGCCCAGGCCCUGGCUGUGAGCUACCGCUUCCUCACUCCCUUCACCUCCAUGAAGCUGAGGGGGCCGGUCCCACGCAUGGAUGGCCUGGAGGAGGCCCACGGCAUGUCGGCUGCCAUGGGACCCGAACCGGUGGUGCAGAGCGUGCGAGGAGCUGGCACGCAGCCAGGACCUUUGCUCAAGAAGCCAUACCAGCCAAGAAUUAAAAUCUCUAAAACAUCAGUGGAUGGUGAUCCCCACUUUGUUGUGGAUUUCCCCCUGAGCAGACUCACCGUGUGCUUCAACAUUGAUGGGCAGCCCGGGGACAUCCUCAGGCUGGUCUCUGAUCACAGGGACUCUGGUGUCACAGUGAACGGAGAGUUAAUUGGGGCACCCGCCCCUCCAAAUGGCCACAAGAAACAGCGCACUUACUUGCGCACUAUCACCAUCCUCAUCAACAAGCCAGAGAGAUCUUAUCUCGAGAUCACACCGAGCAGAGUCAUCUUGGAUGGUGGGGACAGACUGGUGCUCCCCUGCAACCAGAGUGUGGUGGUGGGGAGCUGGGGGCUGGAGGUGUCCGUGUCUGCCAACGCCAAUGUCACCGUCACCAUCCAGGGCUCCAUAGCCUUUGUCAUCCUCAUCCACCUCUACAAAAAGCCGGCGCCCUUCCAGCGACACCACCUGGGUUUCUACAUUGCCAACAGCGAGGGCCUUUCCAGCAACUGCCACGGACUGCUGGGUCAGUUCCUGAAUCAGGAUGCCAGACUCACAGAAGACCCUGCAGGGCCCAGCCAGAACCUCACUCACCCUCUGCUCCUUCAGGUGGGAGAGGGGCCUGAGGCCGUCCUAACAGUGAAAGGCCACCAAGUCCCAGUGGUCUGGAAGCAAAGGAAGAUUUACAACGGGGAAGAGCAGAUAGACUGCUGGUUUGCCAGGAACAAUGCCGCCAAACUGAUUGACGGGGAGUACAAGGAUUACCUGGCAUCCCAUCCAUUUGACACAGGGAUGACACUUGGCCGGGGAAUGUCCAGGGAGCUCUGAAGCUGGCAGCCUUAAAGAUGCAAGUGCAUGAAGGACAGUGAUGUGGGGAGGCCGUGGGGCAGCUCUUUUCAUGGCUUGUACACGCCUCAGCUCCUGGCAAUUAGCUGGACUCCAUGACCCACCCCUGGUGCAGCAUAGAUCCGACGUCUGUCUGGGCGAAGGGUAGGGGUGGGUAGGGGCGGGAAGCCUGAGUGCAAAUGUCAUUUCCCUCUACUGCCUCUUCCUGCCUCUCCCCACCCUGCCCACAUCCACAGAGGGGAGAGAAGGGUCAUAGCUAAAUGCAACAAAGUCUGUAUCUUGUCCCAACCUGCUUUUCUGUUCUGUUAGCAUAUCAUAAAGUAAGCCUUUCUGGUGAAGGAAGGUUGCUAUGAAACUUUUUUUCUUGGUGGAAAUGGACAAGUUUAGGCACUCUGCUUUUUGCCUUACACUAAUGCUUAGAAAGCUGUCUUUUCAGUGGUGUUGCAGCCCCCAGAUGUGUGGCCAACCUCUGCUGCAAAGGAAUCUCUUGCUGAGUCCAGGCCACCAAUCAGGCAAAUAGCCCAUACAUUUGAUCGUUGUAAACCAUGAAGUCUUUUCUUGCAAGACGUUUUUCUUCUGCUGUGGUAUCUUGCCCUUAAAAAUUAGUUUUCAUUAAAAAGAAAUUUGAUUGAAAAUAGAAACAUCUACAGCUCAGAUACUGAUCUCUUUCUAAUGGGCUUUGUAAACCACUUGACUUUGCUAAUGGCUAUUCUCCAAUUUGUUCCAAUAAGCUAAGGGCUUUUCAUACACAGGACAACUCCAUGUGGUUGAUUUUACUGGCAUGUCUUGGUGACGAAGAGUUGGCCAAGUGAAUGAUGCAUCUUUUACUUGGAGCUCUCCAGCCUUUGUCAUAGUUCCCAGACCUUUUUUCCUUGUGGUCAUCCAGGAGGUGAUCAAUUACAUGUGCACAGUGCUAGGACGGGAGGCAGAGCCGGCUCAGAGCAGGUCCACCAGCCCACCUAUAGCAGGAAGCGUGUCGGUGCUUAGGAAAUCUAGGACUUCCAGCUUCCCUCAUGUCAGAUAGAAAAAAAGUCAGGAAACCAGCUCGUGGACAGGGGCUUUGGUUCCAAAACUUGGACAAACCUGAUGCCUUAAGGAAAAGGUUAAGAUGAGAGGGGACUUCCAGAGUCAAUGAACGUCACCCUUCAGCGGACGGAUACCGGGAGCGCUUGGGCGAAACAGCAGAGAAAGAAAGACUGUGGUCGGGGAAGUGGAAUGCUUCGAUGCAGGCCAGAGUUCAAGGCUCUGGGGCUGGCCUCACAAGAGGCUUCUUCCACGGGGCUUGACACCAGAGCAGCCCCCGCGUGAAAUGAGAAGGCAUGCUUAGCACUGGGAGGAAAAGCUGAGUUAAGAAAAUUCUUUAUCAUGUUUGCCUUCCCUGGGGAAACAUUCAGGCAGUAAAAUGACAUCCACGUGUUCCUGUCGGACGCAGCGGCUUCGGGAACAAGUUAGCGCUGGGGGACUAUCUGGGCUCGUCUCUCUCUGCUUCGUGAACCCACCACACCAGGGCCUGUCUGCUGUGCUAUUUAUUUGCCUUCCGUCUUCCCAACCUCAGCUGCCUGUAUUCAUGCCAGAGGUGCAAAGGCUGCCAGCCAGUGCUGCUGACAGAUGCUUUCAGACUGUAGAGCUCAGAGAAAGGGAGCGGCAGCUAGAGGUAGCCAGGGAGCUGGCCAGGCUCCCCGGGGCCUUCCUAUUAUGUAAAUCCCAGCUGGACAGACAGCCCUGGAGCCAGGUGGCCCUGUCCCCUGUGGAGCACUUGGAGCAGUGAUCUGUUGUUCCAGGUGUAAGUCUCGACACUGCAGAAAUGAGGACGUUAUUAGGAAAGACCAGUUCCUACUGCCUGUGUUGCUACUUUAAGAGCUGAGAAAAACAUUCCAAUGAGCUAUCCAUAGCUAACUUGCUUGCUCAGAAAAACAUAAGUAACAAAGUUGAGCUUUCAUUUUUAAAAAUUAUAUUUUACUUUAGAAAAAUAUCACCUUUUUUCUUCCUCUUCUUUACGUGUAGAUCUUUUUUUUUUUUUUCAAAUGGGGUCAGUACCUGAAAGCCCGAAACCCCAUACCAAGCUUAUAGUUAGGACCUUUGCAUUUGAUAAAAAAAAAAUAUAGUAUUUUCUGUUGUCCAGAAAAUCUUCCCAGAUAGGGAAACUGAGGCAGAGAGUGCCGUGGAGUGGUUUUUGCCAAGUCAUACAACAUACUUAAUGCAGGGCUACACUGAACCUCCAGAAUCAUUUUGUUUGCUUUGACCCUGUUUCACCAUCUGGGCAAUCAUUUAUUUUCCUUGAGCAUUUAUAAACCAGGGCGAGGGUUGUUCCAAAAUGAGUAAUUGAAUGAGAUGAAGAAAUAUGUCAUAAUUAGAGGAGAUAAAUCUCCUUGUUAUCACAAUAGUUAAUGUGUCAUGAUCACUGACUAACUGGGACCUUGAACAAGUCAGCAUCUCUGCCUUUCAAAAUGAAGGAACAUUGUUCUCUAUCCUCCCCUGACCCCCGACGGCCCCAUGCUAGGUGCACCAUCUUCCUCCAUUUGACUUUUUAAUGCUUUACAACUUCAGGCUAAAGGGAGGGGAUGUUGGGAGGAGAAACCAUCACAAGAUUCCCUCGGUGCCACAGCUGUGCUGAGGAGGCCGGGGACUGGGAAUCGGAGUGGGCACCUCUGUGUUUCUCUAGGGAGUAACAUUCAACAUUUAAUUGAAUCGUGUGUCCUGAUAGGUGGAUUAGGAACAGGAUUCAUUCCUUUAACUUUAACUUUUGGCUAAACGACAUGCCUUGGAUUGAGUGUAUAUGUCUUCCCCAAAUUCAUAUGUUGAAGCUUAAAUCCUGAAUGUGAUGGUUCUUGGAAUUGGGACCUUUGGAAGGUUAUUGGGUCUUGAGGGCAGAGCCCUCACGAAUGGGAUUAAGGCCCUUAUAAGAAGAGACAUGGGGCCAGGUGCAGUGGCUCACACCUGUAAUCCCAACAUUUUGGGAGGCCGAGAAGGGUGGAUCAUGAGGUCAGGAGAUGGAGACCAUCCUGGCCAACAUGGUGAAACCUCGUCUCUACUAAAAAUACAAAAAUUAGCUGGGCGUGGUGGUGCGUGCCUGUAGUUCCAGCUACUUGGGAGGCUGAGGCAGGAGAAUCGCUUGAACCAGGCAGUCGGAACUUGUAGUGAGCCAAGAUCACGCCACUGCACUCCAGCUGGAGUGACAGAGCCAAACUCCGUCAAAAAAAAACAAAACAAAACAAAAAAAAGACAUGGGAGAGAUGGUGUUUUUCCUCUCCACCACCUGGGGAUACGAUGAGAAGAUGGCCACCUGCAAGCCAGGAAGACGGCCCUCACCAGACACCAUGUCUGCUGGCACCUUGAUCUUGGACCUCCCAGCCUCCAGAACUGUGAGAAAUAAAUGUGUUUUGUUUAAGCUACUCAAGUCUGUGGUAUUCUUGUUAAGGCAGCCCAAGCUGACUAAGACACCAAAUCAUUCAAAACGUUAAUUCUUUUUCUGUUCUUUAAGCUUCCCAGAAUGUACACAAACAAUGCUGUUAUUAAAAUUUAAAGGACUCUUGGAACUGUAGGACAUGAUCCAGCUAAAAUAAAUAACAAAUAACACAGCUAAGCAAAUACUUAUAAAUGUAGCUUUAAAUAUUUAUUUUAGUUUUAAAUAAUUAGUGGGGUACGAGACAGUUCACAUUCAAGAGACAUUUUACUUAGACAAAAAAUUUAUAAGAGAACGAUGCAUAAAAACAAACAACAUAUUGGUCUGUUUAUUUUUCUAAGGGAAAAUGGAAUUGGAGCUGUUGAGAAUAAAACUUGAAGAAUCUAACUGCA